AUGUCUUUCUUCUUUAAUCAUAAACCUGCUAAGAAGCUGCUGAAGUCCAUGGUAGUGACAGGUACAUGUCUGCAUCCUUGUCCUGACCUGCAUCUUCUUCGAUUGUCCCCAUCUGUGUCUCCGACUGGCACUGCCAAACCGGCUUGCUACCUGAUCAGUGUUUAUGACAUAGUUUAUAUCUUUAAAGGGGAAUUAAAAUAUUUCUGGGAAUUUUUAAAGCCGGGCAGGGGCCUCCCAGCUGGGCCCGGAGGCAGCAGGCGGACAAGGGCCAGGAGAGGGCGCGGCGGCGGCGCGGCGGGAAGCGAGGGGCAUCCGGACACUCGCCCCGUUGGCCGCGGCCAUCGGCCCCACGACCUCGACGGCCGUCCUGCCGAAGAACCUGCCGUCGCUGCCCGCCCCCGUGGUGCGGCCCUGACGGUCGCGCAGGCCGACGGACGACAGCGCGCUCCGGAUGAAGUUGGGCGGGUAGCUGCGCUGGCCCUGGAAGAGGCCGGUGGGUCGCCGGUGCUCGCGGGGCGCGGUGGGCACUGUCCGCACCGGGAUGGGGCUCCCCUCCGCGGCGCCUCCCGGCCGGUCCUGCUGCGGCUCCGGGGCCGGAGGGAAUCCGCAGCCGGCCGGGGGCCUCCGCCAGCCUGGCUGCGCGCCGGGACUCCGCCUCGCGCCCGGCCCCCUCUCCAGCAGGUCGGCGCCCCGCGCCCUGCACCCGCCCGCCCGGGGACCGCCCGCCCCUCCUCUCCGCGCCGCCGCUCGCUGACUCCCCCGGCAGGGAUUGCUUCUGCCUCGCUGCCAGGUUUUCUCCCGCCCACCUUCUCCGCUGCCAGACCGCCCGAGCUGCCCUCAGUUUCUCCCCAAGUGGGACUCACUGUCGGGGUGUCCCACAAGCCCGAUCCCAGAGCCUGCUGGCCCGACCCCGGCGACGCCUCCACCCGCGCUCGCCGCCCUCCGGGGCGCACCCUCCGCCAGAAAACAGCCGGCGGGCGGCGAGACUUCGUGCAGAGUGCGGGCUCCUCUCCGGCGCCAGGCCCGUCCCGUCUCCCUGGGAGUGCGCAGCCUACACGCACCAGUUUCUCUUUAGAACAAGGACGGGGAGGGAUUUGCGAGGGGGCUGAAACCUUUUGCCAUCAGCGAACAGCCUCAGCCAAAAACAACCCUGGAAAGGCGAGCUAAGAAUGGUUAUCUCCUGCCAGCGCUGAAAUCGGAGGCCGGGCGCUGCGUGUGUGUGUGUGUGUGUGUGUGUGCGUGUGUGUGUGUGUGUGUGUGUGUGUGUGUACCCUCCCACCCCGACCAUUUGUUGAAGGGAAUCACCACUGUCAGACUUCAAUCCAACAGGACCCACUCGAGCCAUCCACACUUGCCCCAGCCUCCUCCAAAACAGCACACUUUCCGGCUGAAGAAAAGAAGAAUGGUAUUCACGCAGUUCCCAUUUUACAGAUGAAAACAAGAGGACUUUUUCUGUGAAGUCAAGAAAGUGGUUACAAUGGUACUUUCAGCCUGUCCGAAUUAUGUAUUGCCCCUCCCCUUUUUAUUAAUAACAUUGAAGUGUGAUGGGACAACCACUGAAGCCGUCAGUUGAAACCUGCUGGGACUUUUUAGCCAUUCUCUUCAACAUAAAGAAUGGGUGUUUUUGGAGGGGGUGAGAGGAAUGGGGAAAUGUUGUCAAAGAGUACAACGUUUUAGUUGAGACAGGAAGAAUAUAUUUUGUUGAGAUCUACAGCACAGCAUGGUGACUGUAGUUAACAAUGAAGUAUUGUCUAUUUCCAAAUUGCUAAGACAAUAAAUUUCAAAUGUUCUCACCACAAAAAA